GCGUGACGUCGCGCGGGCUCCCGGGCGGGGCGGGUCCGGCCGCCUCCGAGCCCGGCCGGCAGCCCCCGGCCUUAAAGCGCGGGCUGUCCGGAGGGGUCGGCUUUCCCACCGAGGAUUUGGCACUCUGGUGAGGGAAAAGGGCGAAAGAGAAAAGCGAGCAGCCGUCCUUUCACAGCCUCAGAAAGUGCUCGCUUCCCUUCGGGGGCUUUCGCGAAUCCCGAGGCAAUCUCGGAGGCGGUGAGUAAAAGCAAUCUCUUUACCCCACCCGGAGCUCUGGGUCGGAGCGACUGCUUCUGGUCUGGAGCUGCGUGCUUGGCGAAGGGCUCCCGGGGUAGGGGUGGCUCCCGGCUCUGGGGUUGUGUCUGAUGAAAUAGGCCGGGCCCGGGCUACACUCGGUGGUGGUGGACCGGCGGGAGGACGAGCGCUACCUCAGUACUACUUCUGGGUCUCCCGCGCGGGCUGAGGAAGCGCCUUUCGCCGCCAAGCCCGCCCCGCGCAUGCGCCGACUGCGGCUCGCGCGCGCGCUUCGGAGGUUUUUUGGCCAGACCCGCACGCGGAACCGGCGCGGGCACCUGGGGAGAAAUGGAUGGAGAAGGGACCUGGCUGGAAAGCCUUUGCCCCGCUGCUCUGCUCCGCCCAUAAGAGGACCCCUGAAAUGUCCCGUGCAGUUUGUUCAAGUCCCCUGUGUGAUGAAAUGUGCCUCUCGCCUUACCCGUGUGAGAAUACCUGUGGUGUGGCAGCGAGUAUUUUGGUGAGCACCUGCAGUGUAGUGGUUUAUACUAAGGAAUACACACAAAUUACAGGCCUUUGAGCCCAGAAUGCAACUUGGGAGGUAUUUGACCUGUCCAAAGACGACUUGAUACCUCUAUAAUGUAACAGAAAAGGUCAGAAAAUAUUAAGCAAGUAGAAGUGUGGAGCAUAUUAAGCAAGAUGAACAUCUCGGGAAGCAGCUGUGGAAGCCCUAACUCUGCAGAUACAUCUAGUGACUUUAAGGACCUUUGGACAAAACUAAAAGAAUGUCAUGAUAGAGAAGUACAAGGUUUACAAGUAAAAGUAACCAAGCUAAAACAGGAACGAAUCUUAGAUGCACAAAGACUAGAAGAAUUCUUCACCAAAAAUCAACAGCUGAGGGAACAGCAGAAAGUCCUUCAUGAAACCAUUAAAGUUUUAGAAGAUCGGUUAAGAGCAGGCUUAUGUGAUCGCUGUGCAGUAACUGAAGAACAUAUGCGGAAAAAACAGCAAGAGUUUGAAAAUAUCCGGCAGCAGAAUCUUAAACUUAUUACAGAACUUAUGAAUGAAAGGAAUACUCUACAGGAAGAAAAUAAAAAGCUUUCUGAACAACUCCAGCAGAAAAUUGAGAAUGAUCAACAGCAUCAAGCAGCUGAGCUUGAAUGUGAGGAAGACGUUAUUCCAGAUUCACCGAUAACAGCCUUCUCAUUUUCUGGCGUUAACCGGCUACGAAGAAAGGAGAACCCCCAUGUCCGAUACAUAGAACAAACACAUACUAAAUUGGAGCACUCUGUGUGUGCAAAUGAAAUGAGAAAAGUUUCCAAGUCUUCAACUCAUCCACAACAUAAUCCUAAUGAAAAUGAAAUUCUAGUAGCUGACACUUAUGACCAAAGUCAAUCUCCAAUGGCCAAAGCACAUGGAACAAGCAGCUAUACCCCUGAUAAGUCAUCUUUUAAUUUAGCUACAGUUGUUGCUGAAACACUUGGACUUGGUGUUCAAGAAGAAUCUGAAACUCAAGGUCCCAUGAGCCCCCUUGGUGAUGAGCUCUACCACUGUCUGGAAGGAAAUCACAAGAAACAGCCUUUUGAGGAAUCUACAAGAAAUACUGAAGAUAGUUUAAGAUUUUCAGAUUCUACUUCAAAGACUCCUCCUCAAGAAGAAUUACCUACUCGAGUGUCAUCUCCUGUAUUUGGAGCUACCUCUAGUAUCAAAAGUGGUUUAGAUUUGAAUACAAGUUUGUCCCCUUCUCUUUUACAGCCUGGGAAAAAAAAACAUCUGAAAACACUCCCUUUUAGCAACACUUGUAUAUCUAGAUUAGAAAAAACUAGAUCAAAAUCUGAAGAUAGUGCCCUUUUCACACAUCACAGUCUUGGGUCUGAAGUGAACAAGAUCAUUAUCCAGUCAUCUAAUAAACAGAUACUUAUAAAUAAAAAUAUAAGUGAAUCCCUAGGUGAACAGAAUAGGACUGAGUACGGUAAAGAUUCUAACACUGAUAAACAUUUGGAGCCCCUGAAAUCAUUGGGAGGCCGAACAUCCAAAAGGAAGAAAACUGAGGAAGAAAGUGAACAUGAAGUAAGCUGCCCCCAAGCUUCUUUUGAUAAAGAAAAUGCUUUCCCUUUUCCAAUGGAUAAUCAGUUUUCCAUGAAUGGAGACUGUGUGAUGGAUAAACCUCUGGAUCUGUCUGAUCGAUUUUCAGCUAUUCAGCGUCAAGAGAAAAGCCAAGGAAGUGAGACUUCUAAAAACAAAUUUAGGCAAGUGACUCUUUAUGAGGCUUUGAAGACCAUUCCAAAGGGCUUUUCCUCAAGCCGUAAGGCCUCAGAUGGCAACUGCACGUUGCCCAAAGAUUCCCCAGGGGAGCCCUGUUCACAGGAAUGCAUCAUCCUUCAGCCCUUGAAUAAAUGCUCUCCAGACAAUAAACCAUCAUUACAAAUAAAAGAAGAAAAUGCUGUCUUUAAAAUUCCUCUACGUCCACGUGAAAGUUUGGAGACUGAGAAUGUUUUAGAUGACAUAAAGAGUGCUGGUUCUCAUGAGCCAAUAAAAAUACAAACCAGGUCAGACCAUGGAGGAUGUGAACUUGCAUCAGUUCUUCAGUUAAAUCCAUGUAGAACUGGUAAAAUAAAGUCUCUACAAAACAACCAAGAUGUAUCCUUUGAAAAUAUCCAGUGGAGUAUAGAUCCGGGAGCAGACCUUUCUCAGUAUAAAAUGGAUGUUACUGUAAUAGAUACAAAGGAUGGCAGUCAGUCAAAAUUAGGAGGAGAGACAGUGGACAUGGACUGUACAUUGGUUAGUGAAACCGUUCUCUUAAAAAUGAAGAAGCAAGAGCAGAAGGGAGAAAAAAGUUCAAAUGAAGAAAGAAAAAUGAAUGAUAGCUUGGAAGAUAUGUUUGAUCGGACAACACAUGAAGAGUAUGAAUCCUGUUUGGCAGACAGUUUCUCCCAAGCAGCAGAUGAAGAGGAGGAAUUGUCUACUGCCACAAAGAAACUACACACUCAUGGUGAUAAACAAGACAAAGUCAAGCAGAAAGCGUUUGUGGAGCCGUAUUUUAAAGGUGAUGAAAGAGAGACUAGCUUGCAAAAUUUUCCUCAUAUUGAGGUGGUUCGGAAAAAAGAGGAGAGAAGAAAACUGCUUGGGCACACGUGUAAGGAAUGUGAAAUUUAUUAUGCAGAUAUGCCAGCAGAAGAAAGAGAAAAGAAAUUGGCUUCCUGCUCAAGACACCGAUUCCGCUACAUUCCACCCAACACACCAGAGAAUUUUUGGGAAGUUGGUUUUCCUUCCACUCAGACUUGUAUGGAAAGAGGUUAUAUUAAGGAAGAUCUUGAUCCUUGUCCUCGUCCAAAAAGACGUCAGCCUUACAACGCAAUAUUUUCUCCAAAAGGCAAGGAGCAGAAGACAUAGACGUUGAAACAGAAACAGAAGGAUGAAGGACAGUUUUUUCCUUCUUAGUUAUUUAUAGUUAAAGUUGGUACUAAACAUUGAUUUUUUUGAUCUUCUGUAAAUGGAUUUAUAAAUCAGUUUUCUAUUGAAAAUGUUUGUGAUAUUUUGCUUUUGCACCUUUAAAACAAUAAGGCGCUUUCAUUUUGCACUCUAACUUAAGAGUUUUUACUUUAUGUAGUGAUACCUAAUACAAUUUUGAAAAUACAA